AGUGUUCGGCUGGGGCAGGCACGCUGUGGCUGGCUACUUCCCUUCCUCCCAUCCCCCUUGGGCCAAACGGGAUCGGUGCUUCUGGUGAGACGCCUCCCCAUGCACAUCACUCCCAGGUGCCCUAGGGGGCACAUUUCCCACAACUCCCAGAGGGCAGGUUUCUAGAAAGUGCCACCAGUGGGGAGGCGCCACAACUUCACUGCCAUUUUGUGAGGUGCCGCCGUCUCUCCUCCAGCAAGGAAACAAUGACCGAUAAAACAGAGAAGGUGGCUGUAGAUCCUGAAACUGUGUUUAAACGUCCCAGGGAAUGUGACAGUCCUUCGUAUCAGAAAAGGCAGAGGAUGGCCCUGUUGGCAAGGAAACAAGGAGCAGGAGACAGCCUUAUUGCAGGCUCUGCCAUGUCCAAAGAAAAGAAGCUUAUGACAGGACAUGCUAUUCCACCCAGCCAAUUGGAUUCUCAGAUUGAUGACUUCACUGGUUUCAGCAAAGAUAGGAUGAUGCAGAAACCUGGUAGCAAUGCACCUGUGGGAGGAAACGUUACCAGCAGUUUCUCUGGAGAUGACCUAGAAUGCAGAGAAACAGCCUUCUCUCCCAAAAGCCAACAAGAAAUUAAUGCUGAUAUAAAACGUCAAUUAGUGAAGGAACUCCGAUGCGUUGGACAAAAAUAUGAAAAAAUCUUCGAAAUGCUUGAAGGAGUGCAAGGACCUACUGCAGUCAGGAAACGAUUUUUUGAAUCCAUCAUCAAGGAAGCAGCAAGAUGUAUGAGACGAGACUUUGUUAAGCACCUUAAGAAGAAACUGAAACGUAUGAUUUGAGAAUACUUGUCCCUGGAGGAUUAUCACACCCCAAAUGCAUAAUCUCAUUAAUGAUUGAGGAGAGAAAAGGAUCAGAUUGCUGUUUUCUACAAUGGAGCAGGAUAUUGCUGAAGUCUCCUGGCAUAUGUUACCGAAUCAACUGGCCUUCCAGAGGCUAAGAAAUUUCUGUUAGUAAAAGAUGUUCUUUUUCCCAAA